ACAGUCGGCGGCCGCGCGCAGCACGCUCAAGGCCGGGAUGGCGGCGGCGGCGGCGGCAGGAAGCGGGACGCCCCGAGAGGAGGAGGGACCUGCUGGGGAGGCAGCGGCCUCGCAGCCCCAGGCCCCAACGAGUGUGCCUGGGGCUCGUCUCUCGAGGUUGCCUCUGGCGCGAGUGAAGGCCUUGGUGAAGGCAGAUCCCGACGUGACGCUAGCGGGACAGGAAGCCAUCUUCAUUCUGGCACGAGCCGCGGAACUGUUUGUGGAGACCAUUGCAAAAGAUGCCUACUGUUGCGCUCAGCAGGGAAAAAGGAAAACCCUUCAGAGGAGAGACUUGGAUAAUGCAAUAGAAGCUGUGGAUGAAUUUGCUUUUCUGGAAGGUACUUUAGAUUGAUUGCCGAGCGGGGCAGUUUUGUGAGCCUUCAUCUGAAGCCUUCAGUUCACCCCUCUGCACAGGCCUCAGCUUUGAAGAACGGAGUCUUUGCACUUACACACACUCUUCCUGUUCUGCCUUCACCUAUGCCGGGAUAAGCAGAGAUCUCAUCAAUUAGCUCUUCUCUGCAAGGUCUUCCACUAUUUCUGUCUGUCUUCCAUAUCAAGCCUGGAUGCAGCUGCUGCUGCUUAGAGCAGAGAUGAAGAAAGUGUUCUGCAUAAGUGGCUUCCUGAAUGAUGAGGACCAGAAUAAAGGUUUUUGAUCAACCUCAGUCCAGUGUGUUUUAUAAUCUCGCCUUUGUUCCUACCCUGUGACUGGAGAGUCACCAUACCUGGUCACAGACCUUCCUGAUCUUCCCUGCCAGCCAUUCUAACAUACAGUCCUUUCAUUAAUUUUGUUCUUUUAUUUUUCCAGCACAUCACCAGAAAGUGGUUCCAGAAUUUAUGGAACACCACUUGCCCUCAGGAGUUCAAAUAAAUAUGGUCCUAGAUUGAAAGCCAGUUAAAUUUUUUUUAAGUUUUAUUUAUUGACAUAUCCACAUACUCUAUAUUUCACCAAUUUAAAGUGUACAAUUCAGUGGUAUUUAGUAUAUUCACAAAUAUGUACACCAGUCAUCACAGUCGAUUUUAGAACAUUUUAUUUAUUUAUUUAUUAUUAUUAUACUUUA